GUCACUCGGCGGCGGCGGUCGUUCCGGGAGCACUCCGGGCUCCGAUCUCCGGUGUCACAGCAAAGAUCCGCGUCUUUCCGAUGAAUCCAGCCAAUGCCAUCCAGUACACACGCGCAGGACCGGAGGGGCCGGGCCGUGGGAGGAGGCUCUGCGCCGCGGCUGCCCGGGUUCCCCUGCGCUCUGCCCUCGGCCGGGUCGGGUCUCCGCGGGUGCGCGCAGAGGAUCUGGCUCUCGCCGGCGCCUGCCGCCCUUAUAUUCAGCCGGCCGCCCGCAUGGCUAAUGAGAUGCAAAUCAGCAGCCCCCCAAUCUGGCGAGAGCUGUCACAAAGGAGCCACUUUUCCAAACCCUCCUCUCAAUGGAUCGCCAAAUGAUCCUUUCCCGGAGUUCAGUUAUGGGUGUGAGAGGUUUGCAAGGAUUUGUGGGAAGUACCUGCCCACAUAUAUGUACAGUAGUAAAUUUCAAAGAACUGGCAGAGCACCACCGAAGCAAGUAUCCUGGAUGUACCCCUACCAUUGUGGUUGAUGCCAUGUGUUGUCUCAGAUAUUGGUAUACUCCAGAAUCUUGGAUCUGCGGUGGCCAGUGGCGAGAAUACUUUUCUGCUUUGCGAGAUUUUGUUAAAACUUUUACGGCAGCUGGGAUCAAGUUGAUAUUCUUCUUUGAUGGCAUGGUGGAGCAGGAUAAGAGAGAUGAAUGGGUGAAACGAAGGCUCAAGAACAACAGGGAGAUAUCCAGGAUUUUUCAUUACAUCAAGUCACACAAGGAGCAGCCAGGCAGAAAUAUGUUCUUCAUCCCCUCAGGGCUAGCUGUGUUUACACGAUUUGCUCUAAAGACACUGGGCCAGGAAACUUUGUGUUCUUUGCAGGAAGCAGAUUAUGAGGUAGCUUCCUAUGGCCUCCAGCAUAACUGUCUUGGGAUUCUGGGGGAAGACACUGAUUACCUAAUCUAUGACACUUGUCCCUACUUUUCAAUUAGCGAGCUCUGCCUAGAGAGCCUGGACACCGUCAUGCUCUGCAGAGAGAAGCUCUGUGAGAGUCUGGGCCUCUGUGUGGCCGACCUUCCUCUUCUGGCCUGCCUCCUUGGCAACGACAUAAUCCCAGAGGGCAUGUUUGAAAGCUUUAGGUACAAAUGCUUAUCGUCCUACACCUCUGUAAAAGAGAACUUUGACAAAAAAGGUAACAUCAUAUUAGCUGUGUCAGACCAUAUAUCGAAAGUUCUUUACUUGUAUCAAGGUGAGAAAAAAUUAGAAGAGAUAUUACCUCUGGGACCAAACAAAGCUCUUUUUUAUAAAGGAAUGGCAUCAUAUCUUUUACCAGGACAAAAAUCUCCAUGGUUUUUCCAAAAACCCAAAGGUGUAAUAACUUUGGACAAACAAGUAAUAUCCACGAGUUCAGACGCCGAAUCCAGGGAAGAAGUUCCCAUGUGUUCAGAUGCUGAAUCCAGGCAAGAAGUUCCCAUGUGUACAGGCCCUGAAUCCAGGCGAGAAGUUCCCGUGUAUACAGAUUCUGAACCCAGGCAAGAAGUUCCCAUGUGUUCAGACCCUGAACCCAGGCAAGAAGUUCCCACGUGUACAGGCCCUGAAUCCAGGCGAGAAGUUCCCAUGUGUUCAGACCCUGAACCCAGGCAAGAAGUUCCCAUGUGUACAGGCCCUGAAGCCAGGCAAGAAGUUCCCAUGUAUACAGACUCUGAACCCAGGCAAGAAGUUCCCAUGUAUACAGACUCUGAACCCAGGCAAGAAGUUCCCAUGUAUACAGGCUCUGAACCCAGGCAAGAAGUUCCCAUGUAUACAGGCCCUGAAUCCAGGCAAGAAGUUCCCAUGUAUACAGGCCCUGAAUCCAGGCAAGAAGUUUUAAUACGGACAGACCCUGAAUCUAGGCAAGAAAUUAUGUGUACAGGCCAUGAAUCCAAACAGGAAGUUCCCAUAUGUACAGAUCCUAUAUCCAAGCAAGAAGACUCCAUGUGUACACACGCUGAAAUCAAUCAAAAAUUACCUGUAGCAACAGAUUUUGAAUUUAAGCUAGAAGCUCUCAUGUGUACAAACCCUGAAAUUAAACAAGAAGACCCCACAAAUGUGGGGCCUGAAGUAAAGCAACAAGUAACCAUGGUUUCAGACACUGAAAUCUUAAAGGUUGCUAGAACACAUCACGUCCAAGCAGAAAGCUACCUGGUGUACAACAUCAUGAGCAGUGGAGAGAUUGAAUGCAGCAACACCCUAGAAGAUGAGCUUGACCAGGCCUUACCCAGCCAGGCCUUCAUUUACCGUCCCAUUCGACAGCGGGUCUACUCACUCUUACUGGAGGACUGUCAAGAUGUCACCAGCACCUGCCUAGCUGUCAAGGAGUGGUUUGUGUAUCCUGGGAACCCACUGAGGCACCCGGACCUCGUCAGGCCGCUGCAGAUGACCAUUCCAGGGGGAACGCCUAGUUUGAAAAUAUUAUGGCUGAACCAAGAGCCAGAAAUACAGGUUCGGCGCUUGGACACACUCCUAGCCUGUUUCAAUCUUUCCUCCUCAAGAGAAGAGCUGCAGGCUGUCGAAAGCCCAUUUCAAGCUUUGUGCUGCCUCUUGAUCUACCUCUUUGUCCAGGUGGACACGCUUUGCCUGGAGGAUUUGCAUGCGUUUAUUGCGCAGGCCUUGUGCCUCCAAGGAAAAUCCACCUCGCAGCUUGUAAAUCUACAGCCUGAUUACAUCAACCCCAGAGCCGUGCAGCUGGGCUCCCUUCUCGUCCGCGGCCUCACCACUCUGGUUUUAGUCAACAGCGCAUGUGGCUUCCCCUGGAAGACGAGUGAUUUCAUGCCCUGGAAUGUAUUUGACGGGAAGCUUUUUCAUCAGAAGUACUUGCAAUCUGAAAAGGGUUAUGCUGUGGAGGUUCUUUUAGAACAAAAUAGAUCUCGGCUCACCAAAUUCCACAACCUGAAGGCAGUCGUCUGCAAGGCCUGCAUGAAGGAGAACAGACGCAUCACUGGCCGAGCCCACUGGGGCUCACACCACGCAGGGAGGUGGGGAAGACAGGGCUCCAGCUACCACAGGACGGGCUCUGGGUAUAGCCGUUCCAGUCAGGGACAGCCGUGGAGAGACCAGGGACCAGGAAGCAGACAGUAUGAGCAUGACCAGUGGAGAAGGUACUAGUCAACCUCCAGAAAGAGUAUGGAGAGAAAAAGAGGCACACCUGGACGCAGAGCCCUGCCAGCGCCCUCCUCUGCUGUUGCAGCUGCAAGGAGACCAUGCCUGUGGGAGCCAGGCCUCGCUUGCAUGAAGAAGGAACGAUGCCUUUUUCAAUGGUGUCUCCCUCCCAUUGUGCAGAAGAGCUUUUGUUGGCUUCUCUCCCGAGCUUGUGCCUGAUUCUGUGGCCCAAAACAAUCAUUGUUAACAUCUUCAUGUGUUUCAUUCUGAUCUUUCAUUCAUAUAUAUGAUGCCUAGCUAAUUUCAUUUUAAAAUAAAUGGGAAUCUGUUGUAUUCUGAUUUUUUAUUAGCAACACUAGAUUAUGAGGGGUUAUCUCCUGUUAUUAAAAAGUCAGAAAACACUAUACAGUAGUCCUCCCUUAUCUGCGGGGGAGACAUCCCAAGACCCUCAGUGGAUGCCUGAGACUGGAUAGUAUGGAAUCCUACAUAUCUAUACCUUGGCUUUUUCCUCUACGUACAUACCAUGAUAAAGCUUAACAAAGAACAGUGAGAGAUUAACAGCAACCAAUAACUAAUAAAAGCUAUGUGAAUGUGGUCUCUGUCAAAAUAUCGUGCUGUAAUCACCCUUCUUGCUAUCUGAAAACCAAGAAGACCACUAAGUGACUAAUGGUCAGAGAAGCUGGAUGAGGGGCUGAUUCAUGUCCUGGGCAUGACAGAGCGGGAGGCACAAGGUUUCAUCACACUAUUCACAAUGGCGAGCAAGUUAAAACGGAUUUCCCAUUUAAUUUAAUUUUCAGACUUCAGUUGACCAUGAGUAACCGAAACCACAGAAAGUGAAGCUGGGGAUAUUUCAGAAAUUCUUUUCUAAUCAGAAAUUCUAAUCAAACAUAAGUUUCCAACUAUGUGUUCUCUUGGUCCUCAGAAGUGUUUGAAUAGAAAAGUAACAACUAACUUCCCAUCUUUCUGGUGGAAGAGUUAAUUCUGCCUGGAGGGUUCUGCCUGGGAGACAUGACAGCAUGUGUGUGACUCCUGUGUCUGUUUCUGUGGGGUCAUCCCUUUCGUUUCAUUUUGCCAGGGCCUGGCUCAGGAUUUUUUAUGGCAGUGCCUGUGAAGACAAGCCUGGCCCUCCAUCCAGUCACACAGGAAAUCCACAGAGAGCAUGCUGAGAGCAGCCAGCGGCUGGGCUGCCAUCAGGCCUGGUUUAUGAUGCCACAAGUGAAUGGCACGUUUGUUCCUCUUUAUCUCUGAGCAUUGAAGGACUUUUGGUUAAAAAAAAAAAUUAAGUUCAGAGUAAUCCUUUUCAUGGAAGAAUCUUCAGGUCACCAAAGAAUUGAAAUUUUAAGCCCCAGAUUGUACUGAGCUGUACCUGUGGGAAAAGGAAUGGCCAGGGUAUUGAUGAUGGAAAAGAUUCAAAUGAGGAGUUAGAAGGCAAGCCCUCUGUGGGCAGCCGUCUUCCAGAAACCUCGAACUUAUGUCUGUCUCCACCUGAGAAAGGAGAAGAAAAGCUGGUGGUGACCCCUGCUCCUGCUGGGCCAUGCCAUGGCUCUGAAGAUGCCCCGUGUUCUUAGGAGGUGCUCACCCCUGGCACCUAAAGACAUUUCCUUCUGGUUGUUGCUCUUUAAAAACAAAAUAAGCCCCUGAACGUGCUUGCAGGCCAGUUUGUGUGCCUGCACUUGACGAAUUACCUUGACCAACGGGCCAAAGGCACAGAGCUCCAAGGCAUCAUCUUUCCUUAAAAUCCUGAGUGUUUAUUAAAAAGGGACAUGGUCUCUAGGUAUCUUAUUACAUUUGUAUUUCUUACAUUUGAAAUAUCCUAACCGCUCCCUUCGGUUUCUUCUUAAGAACAUUUACAUCUAAUUAUUUUUCGUGCAAGUCUUGUAGGACCCACAUGUUUUCCUAGCUUUGGAAAUCGAUUUUUUUCAUUCCUCUUAUGAGGAUUUCCCUAUGUCAGUAAACAUUAACUUUCUAUUUCUUCCAUUUUUGCUCAUUUGAAACCCCUGCUGCUUCUAGAUCUAUUUCUUUGCACUUGUAUAACUUUGAAAUAAAUUCCUCAUCCCUUAGACUAAGAGAGUGGGUGUCUGUGAAAAUUGUUUUCUCCUUCAUAAUACCUAAAUUCUAGUUUGUCAGUAAAAUAUUUGUGUUUGGUUAACAAGCUCUUAUUUAAGCCAUUGAGUUAGUAUAAUCUUUAUUACCUUUGAAAAACCAGAGAGCUGAAUUUUUUGUCAUUCUAAGUUGUAAGUAACACUGCAGUCAAGUCUUCUGAUGAAAUUUCCAUAUAUCAAAUUGAAAAUAAAGCAAAAUAUAUUUAUUACUCAUAACUAA